AGUGUUCGGGACUGCCUCACGCUGUGCAGAGAAACAAAGAAGGGAGAUCGGAGCGCAGGAGGCACCUAAGAAAGCAAAGAAGAGAGCCGGGGGCGCCAACUCCAACGUGUUCUCCAUGUUCGAACAGACCCAAAUCCAGGAAUUUAAGGAGGCCUUCACUAUCAUGGACCAGAACAGGGAUGGCUUCAUUGACAAGAACGAUCUGAGAGACACCUUUGCUGCCCUUGGGCGAGUGAACGUGAAAAAUGAAGAAAUUGAUGAAAUGAUCAAGGAGGCUCCGGGUCCAAUUAACUUUACUGUGUUCCUCACAAUGUUUGGGGAGAAACUUAAGGGAGCGGACCCUGAGGAAACCAUUCUCAACGCAUUCAAAGUGUUUGACCCUGAAGGCAAAGGGGUGCUGAAGGCUGAUUACGUUCGGGAAAUGCUGACCACGCAGGCGGAGAGGUUUUCCAAGGAGGAGGUUGACCAGAUGUUCGCCGCCUUCCCCCCUGACGUGACUGGCAACUUGGACUACAAGAACCUGGUGCACAUCAUCACCCACGGAGAAGAGAAGGACUAGGAGGGGGCUCGCUGCUGCGCCCUGGGCUCGUCUUUGCAGAGUGGUCCCUGCCCUCAUCUCUCUCCCCCGAGUACCGCCUCUGUCCCUACCUUGUCUGUUAGCCAUGUGGCUGCCCCAUUUAUCCACCUCCAUCUUCUUUGCAGCCUGGGUGGCUAUGGGUACUUCGUGGCCGCACAUCCUACAGUUGGAAAUCCAUCCAGAGGCCAUGUUCCAAUAAACAGGAGGUCGUGUA